AAGUCUACAUGAAAAGGAUGGUUUCUUGGAGCUUCCACAAACUUAAAACCAUGAAACAUCUAUUAUUGCUACUAUUGUGUGUUUUUCUAGUUAAGUCCCAAGGUGUCAACGACAAUGAGGAGGGUUUCUUCAGUGCCCGUGGUCAUCGACCCCUUGACAAGAAGAGAGAAGAGGCUCCCAGCCUGAGGCCUGCCCCACCGCCCAUCAGUGGAGGUGGCUAUCGGGCUCGUCCAGCCAAAGCAGCUGCCACUCAAAAGAAAGUAGAAAGAAAAGCCCCUGAUGCUGGAGGCUGUCUUCACGCUGACCCAGACCUGGGGGUGUUGUGUCCUACAGGAUGUCAGUUGCAAGAGGCUUUGCUACAACAGGAAAGGCCAAUCAGAAAUAGUGUUGAUGAGUUAAAUAACAAUGUGGAAGCUGUUUCCCAGACCUCCUCUUCUUCCUUUCAGUACAUGUAUUUGCUGAAAGACCUGUGGCAAAAGAGGCAGAAGCAAGUAAAAGAUAAUGAAAAUGUAGUCAAUGAGUACUCCUCAGAACUGGAAAAGCACCAAUUAUAUAUAGAUGAGACUGUGAAUAGCAAUAUCCCAACUAACCUUCGUGUGCUUCGUUCAAUCCUGGAAAACCUGAGAAGCAAAAUACAAAAGUUAGAAUCUGAUGUCUCAGCUCAAAUGGAAUAUUGUCGCACCCCAUGCACUGUCAGUUGCAAUAUUCCUGUGGUGUCUGGCAAAGAAUGUGAGGAAAUUAUCAGGAAAGGAGGUGAAACAUCUGAAAUGUAUCUCAUUCAACCUGACAGUUCUGUCAAACCGUAUAGAGUAUACUGUGACAUGAAUACAGAAAAUGGAGGAUGGACAGUGAUUCAGAACCGUCAAGACGGUAGUGUUGACUUUGGCAGGAAAUGGGAUCCAUAUAAACAGGGAUUUGGAAAUGUUGCAACCAACACAGAUGGGAAGAAUUACUGUGGCCUACCAGGUGAAUAUUGGCUUGGAAAUGAUAAAAUUAGCCAGCUUACCAGGAUGGGACCCACAGAACUUUUGAUAGAAAUGGAGGACUGGAAAGGAGACAAAGUAAAGGCUCACUAUGGAGGAUUCACUGUACAGAAUGAAGCCAACAAAUACCAGAUCUCAGUGAACAAAUACAGAGGAACAGCCGGUAAUGCCCUCAUGGAUGGAGCAUCUCAGCUGAUGGGAGAAAACAGGACCAUGACCAUUCACAACGGCAUGUUCUUCAGCACGUAUGACAGAGACAAUGACGGCUGGUUAACAUCAGAUCCCAGAAAACAGUGUUCUAAAGAAGACGGUGGUGGAUGGUGGUAUAAUAGAUGUCAUGCAGCCAAUCCAAACGGCAGAUACUACUGGGGUGGACAGUACACCUGGGACAUGGCAAAGCAUGGCACAGAUGAUGGUGUAGUAUGGAUGAAUUGGAAGGGGUCAUGGUACUCAAUGAGGAAGAUGAGUAUGAAGAUCAGGCCCUUCUUCCCACAGCAAUAGUCCCCAAUACGUAGAUUUUUGCUCUUCUGUAUGUGACAACAUUUUUGUACAUUAUGUUAUUGGAAUUUUCUUUCAUACAUUAUAUUCCUCUAAAACUCUCAAGCAGACGUGAGUGUGACUUUUUGAAAAAAGUAUAGGAUAAAUUACAUUAAAAUAGCACAUGAUUUUCUUUUGUUUUCUUCAUUUCUCUUGCUCACCAAGAAGUAACAAAAGUAUAGUUUUGACAGAGUUGGUGUUCAUAAUUUCAGUUCUAGUUGAUUGCGAGAAUUUUCAAAUAAGGAAGAGGGGUCUUUUAUCCUUGUCGUAGGAAAACCAUGACGGAAAGGAAAAACUGAUGUUUAAAAGUCCACUUUUAAAACUAUAUUUAUUUAUGUAGGAUCUGUCAAAGAAAACUUCCAAAAAGAUUUAUUAAUUAAACCAGACUCUGUUGCAAUAAGUUAAUGUUUUCUUGUUUUGUAAUCCACACAUUCAAUGAGUUAGGCUUUGCACUUGUAAGGAAGGAGAAGCGUUCACAACCUCAAAUAGCUAAUAAACCGGUCUUGAAUAUUUGAAGAUUUAAAAUCUGACUCUAGGACGGGCACGGUGGCUCACGACUAUAAUCCCAACACUUUGGGAGGCUGAGGCGGGCGGUCACAAGGUCAGGAGUUCAAGACCAGCCUGACCAAUAUGGUGAAACCCCAUCUCUACUAAAAAUACAAAAAUUAGCCAGGCGUGGUGGCAGGUGCCUGUAGUCCCAGCUACCUGUGAGGUGGAGAUUGCAUUGAGCCAAGAUCUCAACACUGCACUCCAGCCUGGGCAACAGCGUGAGACUCCACCUCAAAAAAAAAAAAAAAAGAAUCUGACUAUAUACCAUGGAAAAGCCACCACUCUGCCACUUAAAUAAACAUCAGGAUCAGAGAUUCCAAGAGGACAAUCUGCAUCAAGUCUUCACCAAGUGUUUUUUAAGCGAAAUAAUGAAAUAGGGAGCAGAAUAUGCCUGUUGCCCAUAGAAACGAGGUCUAUUCUUGUCCUCAAUUAGGCUUUUUUUUCUUCAUAGUUACACCAGAACUAAAGUAAAAGUGGUUUUUCUGUUCUUUCUACUUCUCCCCAUGAAAUGGGCAUAUCAUCUCAACACUUCACUCCAAGUCGCCACGGGCAACCUUAUGACCCUAGGUCCUCCACCCCUAAUGUAUCAUCAUUGCCACCCAUUUUUAUGGUACUUAUUGUUCUUAAGCUUAUCCUCUUAAUCUUUUCAUGUAAGCAAAGCUCAUUAAUUUCUGUCUUGGAAAUGCUACUACUCUCUUUAAUUACUCACCAAAUCCAACUUUAACUUUUGACCUGGUUUCUCUGCCACAAGUUCUGUCCCACUGGAGCCCAUACUCACCUACCGCUUUGCCAUCACAUUUAACAGAAAACUCUUAUCAACUUACUUCCUGCUUAACAUUAGCUCCUUCCUAUCUAUAUCCAAAUUUCUUAAAUUCAAAUUUUUUAGCUGGAGUAAAAAUGGUCCCAGUACCAUUUCCUGUUCCCUUCACUAUAACCUACAUUUUUGUCACAUUAAGUUUUUCCCCAUUCCAGGACAGGUCAGGCCCUUUAAAAAUUUCAACAGCUUUAUUGAGAUAUAAUUGAUAUAAUUUAAAAAAUCCUGCACAUGUGUCAUGCUGGAGCCCUAUUGAUUCCAACAGGGAUGGCGCCUUGUCCAAGAAGAGACCCAGAGCCAGUGAAUGGGACAUAGGGUUUAUUUAGGACUUAAAUACAGAUGUGGUCCAGUGGCAGUGGGCUGGACAGGACCGCUACUAUUUGUAAAGAGUAUGUAGUUUAUAUAACAUUUCUACUUAGCACUCUCCACUUAGCAACCUCCAUUUAACCCAAAAUAAAAGGCCUUGGUUCCUUGCACAUCCUGAGUUCCAACGGACAGGCAGGGAGUUCAAGUGUCCUUCACAGAUAAGAAGUGAAUCUCUCUGGGUUGGCCAUUCCCGGAUUCCUUAGCUUAGACUCUGAACACAUAUUCUUCUUAGACCAUACAGUCAUUCUCAGGGUAUGCUUGAGUUAAUGCUGUCGGAUGCAUCUGUCAUACAAAGUGUUUAACAUAUACGAUUUCAUGAUUUUGGAAAUAUGCAUACACCCAUGAUAUCACUGGCACAGUCAAGAUAUUAAAUAUAUCCAUCACCUCCAAAA